AGACGGUGCUGGUGACUCGUCCACACUGCUCGCUUCGGAUACUCCAGGCGUCUCCCGUUGCGGCCGCUCCCUGCCUUAGAGGCCAGCCUUGGACACUUGCUGCCCCUUUCCAGCCCGGAUUCUGGGAUCCUUCCCUCUGAGCCAACAUCUGGGUCCUGCCUUCGACACCACCCCAAGGCUUCCUACCUUGCGUGCCUGGAGUCUGCCCCAGGGGCCCUUGUCCUGGGCCAUGGCCCAGAAGGGGGUCCUGGGGCCUGGGCAGCUGGGGGCUGUGGCCAUUCUGCUCUAUCUUGGAUUACUCCGGUCGGGGACAGGAGCGGAAGGGGCAGAAGCUCCCUGCGGUGUGGCCCCCCAAGCACGCAUCACAGGUGGCAGCAGUGCAGUCGCCGGUCAGUGGCCCUGGCAGGUCAGCAUCACCUAUGAAGGCGUCCAUGUGUGUGGUGGCUCUCUCGUGUCUGAGCAGUGGGUGCUGUCAGCUGCUCACUGCUUCCCCAGCGAGCACCACAAGGAAGCCUAUGAGGUCAAGCUGGGGGCCCACCAGCUAGACUCCUACUCCGAGGACGCCAAGGUCAGCACCCUGAAGGACAUCAUCCCCCACCCCAGCUACCUCCAGGAGGGCUCCCAGGGCGACAUUGCACUCCUCCAACUCAGCAGACCCAUCACCUUCUCCCGCUACAUCCGGCCCAUCUGCCUCCCUGCAGCCAACGCCUCCUUCCCCAACGGCCUCCACUGCACUGUCACUGGCUGGGGUCAUGUGGCCCCCUCAGUGAGCCUCCUGACGCCCAAGCCACUGCAGCAACUCGAGGUGCCUCUGAUCAGUCGUGAGACGUGUAACUGCCUGUACAACAUCGACGCCAAGCCUGAGGAGCCGCACUUUGUCCAAGAGGACAUGGUGUGUGCUGGCUAUGUGGAGGGGGGCAAGGACGCCUGCCAGGGUGACUCUGGGGGCCCACUCUCCUGCCCUGUGGAGGGUCUCUGGUACCUGACGGGCAUUGUGAGCUGGGGAGAUGCCUGUGGGGCCCGCAACAGGCCUGGUGUGUACACUCUGGCCUCCAGCUAUGCCUCCUGGAUCCAAAGCAAGGUGACAGAACUCCAGCCUCGUGUGGUGCCCCAAACCCAGGAGUCCCAGCCCGACAGCAACCUCUGUGGCAGCCACCUGGCCUUCAGCUCUGCCCCAGCCCAGGGCUUGCUGAGGCCCAUCCUUUUCCUGCCUCUGGGCCUGGCUCUGGGCCUCCUCUCCCCAUGGCUCAGCGAGCACUGAGCUGGCCCUACUUCCAGGAUGGAUGCAUCACACUCAAGGACAGGAGCCUGGUCCUUCCCUGAUGGCCUUUGGACCCAGGGCCUGACUUGAGCCACUCCUUCCUUCAGGACUCUGCGGGAGGCUGGGGCCCCAUCUUGAUCUUUGAGCCCAUUCUUCUGGGUGUGCUUUUUGGGACCAUCACUGAGAGUCAGGAGUUUUACUGCCUGUAGCAAUGGCCAGAGCCUCUGGCCCCUCACCCACCAUGGACCAGCCCAUUGGCCGAGCUCCUGGGGAGCUCCUGGGACCCUUGGCUAUGAAAAUGAGCCCUGGCUCCCACCUGUUUCUGGAAGACUGCUCCCGGCCCGCCUGCCCAGACUGAUGAGCACAUCUCUCUGCCCUCUCCCUGUGUUCUGGGCUGGGGCCACCUUUGUGCAGCUUCGAGGACAGGAAAGGCCCCAAUCUUGCCCACUGGCCGCUGAGCGCCCCCGAGCCCUGACUCCUGGACUCCGGAGGACUGAGCCCCCACCGGAACUGGGCUGGCGCUUGGAUCUGGGGUGGGAGUAACAGGGCAGAAAUGAUUAAAAUGUUUGAGCACAA